AGAGAUUGGGCUGUUUCCUCACUGAUACAUAUCCCUUCACACUUCUAUAAUUUAACUCUCUCAACUGCAUGUGAAAGAUCUUAGCUGAAGAUGACUGACAGUGUUAUUUAUUCCAUGUUAGAGUUGCCUACGGCAACCCAAGCCCAGAAUGACUAUGGACCACAGCAAAAAUCUUCCUCUUCCAGGCCUUCUUGUUCUUGCCUUGUGGCAAUAGCUUUGGGGCUUCUGACUGCAGUUCUUCUGAGUGUGCUGCUAUACCAGUGGAUCCUGUGCCAGGGCUCCAACUACUCCACUUGUGCCAGCUGUCCUAGCUGCCCAGACCGCUGGAUGAAAUAUGGUAACCAUUGUUAUUAUUUCUCAGUGGAGGAAAAGGACUGGAAUUCUAGUCUGGAAUUCUGCCUAGCCAGAGACUCACACCUCCUUGUGAUAACGGACAAUCAGGAAAUGAGCCUGCUCCAAGUUUUCCUCAGUGAGGCCUUUUGCUGGAUUGGUCUGAGGAACAAUUCUGGCUGGAGGUGGGAAGAUGGAUCACCUCUAAACUUCUCAAGGAUUUCUUCUAAUAGCUUUGUGCAGACAUGCGGUGCCAUCAACAAAAAUGGUCUUCAAGCCUCAAGCUGUGAAGUUCCUUUACACUGGGUGUGUAAGAAGGAAACAGGCGUACAUCAGGGGCUGUUCUUUUGCUGCAAAUGAAGUUGAUGGAAUUACACUGUGAUACGACUGACUAGCCACCACCAGGGUAGGCGAGAUGGCCGCCUCCAUGUCCUUCGUCUCCAAGUUUCUCCACAGCAAAGGGCUCACGAACGGGCAACAGCUGCAGACCUUCAGCCACAGCCUGCAGGAACUGCUGACAGAACAUUAUAAACAUCACUGAUUCCCAGAAAAGCCAUACAAAAGAUCAAGUUAUCUUUGUAUUCGCAUCAACCAUGAAAUGGAUCCCCUGGACAGGCAGCACAGUGGAUUGGACCGAGCAGUCAGGAGCUGUUCAAGCUUUUCCCAAGUGAACUCACACUCUGGGUUGGACUCACGCUCACCUCAACCUAUGAGAUGUCUGUCCUGCAGAAUUGGAGAAGAUGGCUCCAUCUGUGUGCUGUAUGAAAGCCCCACCAGCAGGGGGUAGCACUCAAAACAGCACCGACAUACAAAUGGUAGACAGCUGAAUAAACUGUAAGGACGAAUUUCUCUUGGGCAGAACCAGCCCUUCCAAAAACUACAGUAUGAUGACUGUAUCAGGUUAAGAUGGAUCAUCUUAUAGUGCAUGGAUAAAUUUGAUUUUGGCUUUGGGUGGGCUCCUAUUGGGGAUGGAUUAUGGAAUUUAAACCAUGUCACAGCUGUGAAGAUCCGGCACAAGAUAGAGUGGUAAACAUUUUUUUAAAAGUGACAGUGCCAUAGUUUGUACAGUAUCUUUCAAUAAUUUAAUAGCCUAUGAGUCCAAGUAAAUGAUCACUUUAUUUGCUAGGGAGUGAAGUCCUAGAGUGAUUUCAGCUUCUCCCAGACAUACUUAAAUUUUUACAUCAAUUCCUUUAAAGAAAAUCCGUAUGUCAAAGAACCUUUCUCUGUAGUAGAUCUCGCAGAGGAAUUUGAACUAUCACACUUGAAAAUUAUUGUUUACCUUUUUGGCAGCUCAAUAGGGGAGCUCAACGUUUUAAACAUAGUAGUACUGGAAAUUUUACGACAAGACUUUUACCUAGCAAAUAUUUCUAAAUGUACAUAAAGACAAGCUAGCAAACAUGACCUGGGAAAAUGGUCAGACUUUGUAUUGUGUUUUUGACCUUGAAAGUAGCAAGUGACCAGAAUCUGCCAUGGCAACGGGUUUUUAAAAAGACCCUUAGAAAGACUGUUUCAACUGUGGUGUUGGCACCAGCCAGCUCUACGUACAUUUGCUAGCUUGUAGUUUUCUAAGACUGAGUAAACUUCUAUUUUAGAAAUUGGAGGUCUGGUUUGUAACUUUCCUGGGUAAAAGUAUUUUCAUCUAUUUUGUGAACUUUGUUAAUCAUCUUUUAUUUGGUAAAUUAUGAAUGGGUAUACAUUUGUACAGUUCGUGUAUAUUGAUUGUGGCAAAGUUGUAUUGAUUUCUAUAUUUUGGAUGAGAAAUUUUUCUUCUGUAAUAAAUUGUUUCUUAUCUUGGCAUUUAAAAAAG